UGGGAUUACAGAUGUGAGCCACCACACCCAGCCUUAAUAGUUUUUUUGUCUAGUUACACUUUUUCUUUUAGAGAACUUGAAACCCAUUAAUGCACAUGUACAUACAUAAUCCACACAUAUAUGUAUAUGUAUGUGUGUGUGUGUAUAUGGCAUAUCCAUUUAUCCACAUACUAUACAUACAUGCCUUACACUAUAGUUUCCUGAAGCUUACAUCACAGGCACAGUCAUGUCCACAUUCCAGUAAUGCUUAUCAUUCCACGACCGAUAUGGCUUAAUGUAUGCUUUAGUUUUCAGAAUAUAUCACUUACUCCUACGAAUCAGUAAGGAAAGGACCAGCAGCUAAUAGAAAAUGUGACAAAGAUUUGAAAAGGAGGAAUCAUAAAAGGUGCCCACCUGUAUGGUCAGGUUGAAGCAAAUUAAAGCCACAAUGAGAUGCUGCUGCCUUAUACCUGCCAGGCAGCAGAAGUGUUAAAAUUUGACCAUAUCAAGUUGGCGGGAUAAAGAUCAGCAGGGACUCAUGUUCGCUGCUGGCAGGAUGACCUUGUCACCGGCACUUGGGAGGUGCUGCUGUGUGCACGGGCAUCUGCUCCUGGGAUUGUUCCAACGAAACACCUGCCUGUGCGGCUCAGGAGAGGUGACAGCGACAGCAGCACCAUUUAGUAGCCAGCCUGGGAGCCGAUACACAUCCACACCCCGUCAGUGGCUGCAUGCAGUGUAUCUGACGGGACACCAGGUGAAGGGGGCCCAGCUGCACAUGGGGACAGAGGCAGACUUGGCUGCACGUCAGCAGAGAAGUCUCACAGCAUCGUCGGUGUCAAGUUCAAAACACGGAACACGCAGCAGUGUGGCUCAGGGCCACACACGGGGCACAGCCAUCAGGACAAGCAAAGACCAAGAAGCACCAAGUCCAAGUUAGGCAGCAUCUCAGGCCGGGGCACCAAGGAAGGGCACAGCAGCGCCGUGGUGACCGGGUCCCAGUACCAUCCUGGGUGGCCGCCACCGGCCGUUUGUGUCUUCCGUUCACACGAUUACAAACGCUGCGUUCUGCCCACACACAUCUUCAGUCCCAGAUGUGAGAAGGUUACGUUUUUCUCUCGUCCCAGCUGUGUGGACAGUGCCACACGCCCUCCUGGACAACGACGGCUCUUGCGUGCAUUUUCCAGUGUUGCUUUUGUCAGAGAGGCCAGCAGAGCCACGGUUCUUCCAGAACCAGCCCUGAGCUGAGUGAGGAGUGCCCAGGAGAGAUGGUGAAAAUGACAAAGUCCAAAACUUUCCAAGCGUAUCUGCCGAACUGUCACCGAACGUACAGCUGUAUCCACUGCAGAGCACACCUGGCCAAUCAUGACGAGCUCAUCUCCAAGUCCUUUCAGGGGAGCCAGGGACGCGCCUACCUCUUCAAUUCCGUGGUGAACGUGGGCUGCGGCCCUGCAGAGGAGAGGGUCCUUCUCACCGGGCUGCAUGCGGUUGCCGACAUCUACUGCGAGAACUGCAAGACCACGCUCGGGUGGAAAUACGAGCAUGCCUUUGAGAGCAGUCAGAAAUAUAAGGAAGGAAAAUUCAUCAUUGAGCUUGCUCAUAUGAUCAAAGACAAUGGCUGGGAGUAAUGUGCGAACUUUCCCUUCUCCUUUGAAUGCUGUUUUGUGAAAGAAACUGUGAAUGUAAUGGAAACGUAGGAGCAUCUGGUGACAGCCUUUCUUGCCCUCUGACCUCAAAGGCUAGCUGCGCAUAGCUCUUGACACUCUCGGCCAUCUCUGUGGGUAAGGUGUCCCUCGGAUCUGUCCUCUUCGUGUACACAGUUGUUUCUGAAAAUUUUCAAUGAGCUUUUUCUAACUUCUCAAGUUCUAGAGAAAGAAUUAACCAACUGAUGACUUACCUGCCUAGUUAAUAUCUUCCUUUCACCUUUGUCUUCAAUAUAGUUGGGCUCUGCUUUUUUAAGGUUCAGUUGAAAACCAAACUGGGGCCGGGUGCGGUGGCUCACGCCUGUAAUCCCAGCACUUUGGGAGGCCAAGAUGGGUGGAUCACCUGAGGUCAGGAGUUCUAGAUCAGCCUGGCCAACAUGGUGAAACCCCAUCUCUACUAAAAAUACGAAAAUUAGCCGGGCAUGGUGGCGAGUGCCUGUAAUCUUAGCUACUCAGGAGGCUAAGGCAGGAGAAUCACUUGAACCUGGGACACGGAGGUUGCAGUGAGCUAAGAUCAUGCCAUCGCACUCCAGCCUGGGGGACAAAAGUGAGACAUCGUCUCAAAAAAAAAAAAAAAAGCUGGGUAUGGUGGCGCAUGCCUUUAAUCCCAGCUACUCGGGAGGCUGAGGCACGAGAAUCACUUGAACCCAGGAGGCGGAGGUUGCAGUGAGCCAAGAUCGCGCCACUGCACUCCAGCCUGGCAAUAGGGCGAGACUCCGUCUCAAUUUAAAACAAGAGAGAACCAGACUGAGUCUCUGAAGACCACAGGGACAGGGUCUCUUUAGAUAGCAAGUCUCACCAUUCCCUUUUUUAGAGAAAAGGUAUUGUAGCCCACCCUCCACCCCGCUGUUUUUCUUAAAUUUGCAGAACUUCAAAUUGGCUAUUCCUCUUGCAAAUGAACCCUUAAAGUACAGUGUUAUUUAAGAAUCUUCCAGAGGCAGUCAACAGACUUAUACACUAAGGGCAUUUUUGGUUUUUAGCUUGUUCAAAAACAGAGGCCAGCACAGAUGACAUUUUAGAUACACUCUAAAUUGAGAAUGGUGUCUAGUGGAACAUGUUUAUUUAAGCCAGUAGAUUCCUUAUCUAGAAAGCAGGUGAGCUAGCCCUUAGAGAAGGCUGUCCCGGGGCCCGCAGAGGUGCCCUUACUGAGGUGACAGCCUCACAGGGUCUGGUACCAGGGGUUGUGCCCUCAGCAGUGACAGCAGCUUAGGUGUCAGGCAGUUGCUGAGUGGCUGGUCCAUGUCUAUAGAGUAACACACUGGACCGAGGAAAAGUCAGAUUUCAUUUUCUACCCUGGAUGUACUUGAAGAAAAAGAAUUAUUUUUGCAUAUGAAAGAGGCCAGAACCCACAGGAAAAACUUCAAAACUUGACAUUUGCCAGAAUGUUUAAAAUUUGUUCAGAAAAGGUUAAAGCAACAAGUUUAGCCUUUGUGCAUGAAGACGCCUGGCCUGCUAGACGCGUUGCCCGUCCCUGCGUGGUGCUGUCCCAUGUCACUUGAACUGAUAGAGGGGCCUGUGCAAUCUCCUAAGGCCUGUGUUUCUGCCAUAUAUUUUAUUAUAAAUUACAAUCCACUCAUCCACCUGCCCUCCACCAGGAGUGGGCACCCCAUAAGGGUUUAGGCCACUUUGCAGAGGAUGGAGGUCAAAAACCACUCCCAGAUAAGUUUGGUUUUCAACAUUUAGUAACUUGUCUCAGGGCAGAGGGCAGGCAGGGGGACCGAGGGGCAGCAGAUAGGAGAGCACUGAGCCCGGAUAGUUCUCAGCCUGGCAAGUGGCUCUGAAGCUGCCUUCAGACAAGGCUAGUCUAGGGGCAAGAGUGCGAGCUGGCUGACAAUAAGAACGUGGCCACCUGCCCAGCUUCACACCUCCCCCGACUUCAGCCCUUCCUAAACCCAGACCUGCGGUCCAGGCAGGCACUGGGCUGUGCCCACUCGAGCUCACUGCCCACACACAGCAUGCCUUUGGGUGCCAUCUCUUUGCCCAAGCCUGGAAGCCUUGGCAGGUGGGAAAUGCCGCUGCCCUGGUGGGCAUGGCACUGAGAUGCAUCCACUCAGCAGGAGUGACAGAGGCAGAAGUUCCUUUAAAGCACAUCUUCCACUUAGGAAAGGAAGGAAAUCUUUGUACUGUCUUGGAAGCCUCCACAUCCGGCUAUGGCCCUGCAAGCUGCUUUAUCCCUGCGCUAGUCUCCCCCGAGGGUUUAGGCUGGCCCAGCACAUCCUGUCCUCCUGAGCUCGCGUGCAGCCACCCAGAGCGCAGGGGUCACUGCACGCUGCAGGGCUCUUGCUGCCAUGGUCUCAAGCCUGAAGAGGCUCCGCCCACAAGCUGGCCCAUGAAGUUAGCAAUGCCUGUGGCUUCAGUCAAUUGUCUUGAGACUGUGAAGAGGCUGAAAGACACCUUCCCGGGUGGAAGAAGGAGUUCACUGAAAACUUAUCUUAAACUGACCCUUCCCUUUGAGUGAGUCUUCAUUCCUCUCCCAUGUGGGAACCCAGCCUCCGAUGCCCCGGGGACUAGGGGAAACAGUUGGAGGUUCGUGCCGUCCCCAGCCUGCCACGGGUGCGAGGACAGCCAAGUCCUGAGUGACUCAAGAUGCUUCACUUACAUGGAAGAAACUUCUAAAACUCUACCGAGUGGUUUUUGUAUAUACUAAAGUUCUAUUUAGAGCUUUUCUGUUUUGGGCAAGUUCGCUGCUCCUUCUAUUUGGGCACUUUGGUUUUUGUACUGUCUUUUGUGACGGCAUUGAUUGAACAUUUUUUACUAGUAGUCUUAUGACUUUUGUAUUUUUUUUUUUUUUUGUAAUUUAUACCAACAACACUUUUAUCACUUUUUUUUUGUUGGGCUUCUGCAAAAUACAAGCUCAUUUUUAAACCAAAUGAACAGACCAUGAGCUGGCUUCAGGGGAAGUGCUAUUCACAGGACCAUAUCCACCACCCUCUUAAAUUCCUAAACAAUAUCAUCUAGGACUUCUAUUUAAGUUAUUUAAAAUAAAUCUUCCUUGAGAGCCUUGGGAGGUGAUGUCAGGGUUAUAAAUGGCACAGUGCAUUUGCUGUAGGAAUGUGGUUUGGCAUUGUUUUAUACACACAGUAUUUUUUAUACCUUAAUGCUUAUUCUUGAUGGCAUCUGUCAGAUAUUAGAAUUGAAAAUAAGAAUCUUCCCAAAAUCCUUUAAUUUACCUGAUGCCCUCAUCAGGUCGUUAAAAAUUCAAAUGGUUUUAAUAGCUAAAAAACUACAAAUUAAGCUCUAAAACAAACAAACUACAGAAAUGUAAACCUUCAUUUGCCAAAGGUCCUUGGUGGCCUGUCCCCUGCCCUGGGAGCAGAUGGCCCUGAAGCCCUUCCCUCACUGUGCAGGCCACCGGGUGAGGCUGGACGGUCACCCAUGGUGGCUUCACUGCAAGGAGCAGGACUGCCGAGCUCAAGCACGGGGCCUUCAGCUUCCCCUGUCCUCUGGCCACACCGCCAGCCCUUGGUCCUUAUCUGUGUGAGGUUUACAAAUAAAGCUUCUGAUGUCAAAUGUUUAAA